AGACGGCGGUGGGACGGCCAGGCCCCGGCCCCGCCAGUGUGUCCGCCCGGCCCCGCGUCCCGGAGCGCCCGCACCCGGCCCCGCCGCCGCCUCAGAGCAAGAAAGCUUUCUGCUCAGCCAUGGCUACGAGUCCACGCCUUAAUGCACCCCACAGCCAGCGGCAGUGGCAGUGACAACAGCGGGACCUGCCUUUGAAGAUCGGCUGCUGCAAGGGUUGAUGGCUGGCAUGUCGCAAAGACCCCCCAGCAUGUACUGGUGUGUGGGGCCGGAGGAGUCAGCUGUGUGUCCAGAACGUGCCAUGGAGACGCUUAACGGUGCCGGGGACACGGGCGGCAAGCCGUCCACGCGGGGCGGUGACCCUGCAGCGCGGUCCCGCAGGACGGAAGGCAUCCGCGCCGCGUACAGGCGGGGAGACCGCGGCGGCGCCCGGGACCUGCUGGAGGAGGCCUGCGACCAGUGCGCGUCCCAGCUGGAAAAGGGCCAGCUUCUGAGCAUCCCGGCAGCCUAUGGGGAUCUGGAGAUGGUCCGCUACCUACUCAGCAAGAGACUGGUGGAGCUGCCCACCGAGCCCACGGAUGACAACCCAGCCGUGGUGGCAGCGUAUUUUGGACACACGGCAGUUGUGCAGGAAUUGCUUGAGUCCUUACCAGGUCCCUGCAGUCCCCAGCGGCUUCUGAACUGGAUGCUGGCCUUGGCUUGCCAGCGAGGGCACCUGGGGGUUGUGAAGCUCCUGGUCCUGACGCACGGGGCUGACCCGGAGAGCUACGCUGUCAGGAAGAAUGAGUUCCCUGUCAUCGUGCGCUUGCCCCUGUAUGCGGCCAUCAAGUCAGGGAAUGAAGACAUUGCAAUAUUCCUGCUUCGGCAUGGGGCCUAUUUCUGUUCCUACAUCUUGCUGGAUAGUCCUGACCCCAGCAAACAUCUGCUGAGAAAGUACUUCAUUGAAGCCAGUCCCUUGCCCAGCAGUUAUCCGGGAAAAACAGCUCUCCGUGUGAAAUGGUCCCAUCUCAGACUGCCCUGGGUAGACCUAGACUGGCUCAUAGACAUCUCCUGCCAGAUCACGGAGCUCGACCUUUCUGCCAACUGCCUGGCGACCCUCCCCUCGGUUAUCCCCUGGGGCCUCAUCAAUCUCCGGAAGCUGAACCUCUCCGACAACCACCUGGGGGAGCUGCCUGGCGUGCAGUCAUCGGACGAAAUCAUCUGUUCCAGGCUACUUGAAAUUGACAUUUCCAGCAACAAGUUGUCCCACCUCCCUCCUGGAUUCUUGCACCUCUCAAAACUUCAAAAACUGACAGCUUCAAAAAAUUGUUUAGAAAAAUUGUUCGAAGAAGAAAAUGCCACUAACUGGAUAGGUUUACGGAAGCUACAGGAACUUGAUAUAUCUGACAAUAAAUUGACAGAACUCCCUGCCCUGUUCCUUCACUCUUUCAAGUCCCUCAAUUCUCUGAAUGUCUCCAGAAACAACCUGAAGGUGUUUCCAGAUCCCUGGGCCUGCCCUUUGAAAUGUUGUAAAGCUUCCAGAAAUGCCCUGGAAUGUCUGCCAGACAAAAUGGCUGUCUUUUGGAAAAAUCACCUGAAGGAUGUGGAUUUCUCAGAAAACGCACUCAAAGAAGUUCCCCUGGGACUUUUCCAGCUUGAUGCCCUCAUGUUCUUGAGGUUACAGGGGAACCAGCUGGCGGCACUUCCACCUCAAGAGAAGUGGACCUGCAGGCAGCUCAAAACCCUGGAUCUCUCCAGAAACCAACUUGGCAAAAAUGAAGAUGGACUGAAAACGAAGCGUAUUGCCUUUUUCACCACCAGAGGUCGCCAGCGCUCCGGGACUGAGGCAGCAAGUGUGCUGGAAUUUCCGGCCUUCCUAAGUGAGUCUUUGGAAGUCCUUUGCCUGAACGACAACCACCUCGACACAGUCCCUCCCUCGGUUUGCCUACUGAAGAGCUUAUCAGAGCUCUACUUGGGAAACAACCCUGGCCUCCGGGAGCUCCCUCCUGAGCUGGGGCAGCUGGGCAACCUCUGGCAGCUGGACACUGAAGACCUGACCAUCAGCAAUGUGCCUGCAGAAAUCCAAAAAGAAGGCCCCAAAGCAAUGCUGUCUUACCUGCGUGCUCAGCUGCGGAAAGCGGAAAAGUGCAAGCUGAUGAAGAUGAUCAUCGUGGGUCCCCCGCGCCAGGGCAAGUCCACCCUCCUGGAGAUCUUACAGACGGGGAGGGCCCCCCAGGUGGUGCAUGGAGAGGCCACCAUCAGGACCACCAAGUGGGAGCUCCAGAGGCCGGCUGGCUCGAGAGCCAAGGUUGAGUCCGUGGAGUUCAACGUCUGGGACAUCGGGGGACCGGCCAGCAUGGCCACUGUCAACCAGUGCUUCUUCACGGACAAGGCCCUGUACGUGGUGGUCUGGAACCUGGCGCUGGGGGAGGAGGCCGUGGCCAACCUCCAGUUCUGGCUGCUCAACAUCGAGGCCAAGGCCCCAAACGCCGUGGUGCUGGUGGUCGGGACGCACCUGGAUUUAAUUGAAGCCAAGUUCCGUGUGGAAAGGAUUGCAACGCUGCGUGCCUAUGUGCUGGCACUCUGCCGCUCCCCCUCCGGCUCCAGGGCCACAGGCUUCCCAGACAUCACCUUCAAACACUUACAUGAGAUUUCCUGCAAGAGCCUGGAAGGUCAGGAAGGGCUGCGACAGCUGAUUUUCCACGUCACGUGCAGCAUGAAGGACGUGGGCAGCACCAUCGGCUGCCAGCGACUGGCAGGGCGGCUGAUCCCCAGGAGCUACCUGAGCCUGCAGGAGGCCGUGCUGGCAGAGCAGCAGCGCCGCAGCCGGGACGACGACGUGCAGUACCUGACGGACAGGCAGCUGGAGCAGCUGGUGGAGCAGACGCCCGACAACGACAUCAAGGACUACGAGGACCUGCAGUCAGCCAUCAGCUUCCUCAUAGAAACCGGCACCCUGCUCCAUUUCCCGGACACCAGCCACGGCCUGAGGAACCUCUACUUCCUCGACCCUAUUUGGCUCUCCGAAUGUCUGCAGAGGAUCUUUAAUAUUAAGGGCUCUCGGUCAGUGGCCAAGAAUGGGGUGAUCAGAGCAGAAGACCUCAGGAUGCUGCUGGUGGGGACUGGCUUCACGCAGCAGACGGAAGAGCAGUACUUCCAGUUCCUGGCCAAGUUUGAGAUCGCCCUGCCCGUCGCCAAUGACAGCUACCUCCUGCCCCAUCUCCUUCCAUCUAAACCUGGCCUGGACACCCACGGUAUGCGGCACCCCACAGCCAACACCAUUCAGAGGGUAUUUAAGAUGAGCUUCGUUCCCGUUGGCUUCUGGCAAAGGUUUAUAGCACGGAUGCUGAUCAGCCUGGCGGAGAUGGACCUGCAGCUUUUUGAAAACAAGAAGAAUACUAAAAGCAGGAACAGGAAAGUCACCAUUUACAGUUUUACAGGAAACCAGAGAAAUCGCUGUAGCACAUUCAGAGUGAAAAGAAAUCAGACCAUCUAUUGGCAGGAAGGGCUCCUGGUCACUUUUGAUGGGGGCUACCUCAGUGUGGAAUCUUCCGACGUGAACUGGAAAAAGAAGAAAAGCGGAGGAAUGAAAAUUGUUUGCCAAUCAGAAGUGAGGGACUUCUCAGCCAUGGCUUUCAUCACGGACCACGUCAAUUCCUUGAUUGAUCAGUGGUUUCCCGCCCUGACAGCCACAGAGAGCGACGGGACGCCACUCAUGGAGCAGUACGUGCCCUGCCCGGUCUGCGAGACAGCCUGGGCCCAGCACACGGACCCCAGUGAGAAAUCAGAGGAUGUGCAGUACUUCGACAUGGAAGACUGUGUCCUGACGGCCAUCGAGCGGGACUUCAUCUCCUGCCCCAGACACCCGGACCUCCCCGUGCCGCUGCAGGAGCUGGUCCCUGAACUGUUCAUGACCGACUUCCCGGCCAGGCUCUUCCUGGAGAACAGCAAGCUGGAGCACAGCGAGGACGAGGGCAGCGUCCUGGGCCAGGGCGGCAGUGGCACCGUCAUCUACCGGGCCCGGUACCAGGGCCAGCCUGUGGCCGUCAAGCGCUUCCACAUCAAAAAAUUCAAGAACUUUGCUAACGUACCGGCAGACACCAUGCUGAGGCACCUGCGGGCCACCGAUGCCAUGAAGAACUUCUCCGAGUUCCGGCAGGAGGCCAGCAUGCUGCACGCGCUGCAGCACCCCUGCAUCGUGGCGCUCAUCGGCAUCAGCAUCCACCCGCUCUGCUUCGCCCUGGAGCUCGCGCCGCUCAGCAGCCUCAACACCGUGCUGUCCGAGAACGCCAGAGAUUCUUCCUUUAUACCCCUGGGACACAUGCUCACCCAAAAAAUAGCCUACCAGAUCGCCUCGGGCCUGGCCUACCUGCACAAGAAAAACAUCAUCUUCUGUGACCUGAAGUCGGACAACAUUCUGGUGUGGUCCCUUGACGUCAAGGAGCACAUCAACAUCAAGCUAUCUGACUACGGGAUUUCGAGGCAGUCAUUCCAUGAGGGCGCCCUAGGCGUGGAGGGCACUCCUGGCUACCAGGCCCCAGAGAUCAGGCCUCGCAUUGUAUAUGAUGAGAAGGUAGAUAUGUUCUCCUAUGGAAUGGUGCUCUACGAGUUGCUGUCAGGACAGCGCCCUGCACUGGGCCACCACCAGCUCCAGAUUGCCAAGAAGCUGUCCAAGGGCAUCCGCCCGGUUCUGGGGCAGCCGGAGGAAGUGCAGUUCCGGCGACUGCAGGCGCUCAUGAUGGAGUGCUGGGACACUAAGCCAGAGAAGCGACCGCUGGCCCUGUCGGUGGUGAGCCAGAUGAAGGACCCGACUUUUGCCACCUUCAUGUAUGAACUGUGCUGUGGGAAGCAGACAGCCUUCUUCUCAUCCCAGGGCCAGGAGUACACCGUGGUGUUUUGGGAUGGAAAAGAGGAGUCCAGGAACUACACGGUGGUGAACACAGAGAAGGGCCUCAUGGAGGUGCAGAGGAUGUGCUGCCCUGGGAUGAAGGUGAGCUGCCAGCUCCAGGUCCAGAGAUCCCUGUGGACAGCCACCGAGGACCAGAAAAUCUACAUCUACACCCUCAAGGGCAUGUGCCCCUUAAACACACCCCAACAGGCCUUGGAUACUCCAGCUGUCGUCACCUGCUUCUUGGCCGUGCCUGUUAUUAAAAAGAAUUCCUACCUGGUCUUAGCGGGCCUCGCCGAUGGGCUUGUGGCUGUGUUUCCCGUGGUGCGGGGCACCCCAAAGGACAGCUGCUCCUACCUGUGCUCACACACAGCCAACAGGUCCAAGUUCAGCAUCGCGGAUGAAGACGCACGGCAGAACCCCUACCCAGUGAAGGCCAUGGAGGUGGUCAACAGCGGCUCUGAGGUCUGGUACAGCAAUGGGCCGGGCCUCCUUGUCAUCGACUGUGCCUCCCUGGAGAUCUGCAGGCGGCUGGAGCCCUACAUGGCCCCCUCCAUGGUUACGUCAGUCGUGUGCAGCUCUGAGGGCAGAGGGGAGGAGGUCGUCUGGUGCCUGGAUGACAAGGCCAACUCCUUGGUGAUGUACCACUCCACCACCUACCAGCUGUGUGCCCGGUACUUCUGCGGGGUCCCCAGCCCCCUCAGGGACAUGUUUCCCGUGCGGCCCUUGGACACGGAACCCCCGGCAGCCAGCCACACGGCCAACCCAAAGGUGCCUGAGGGGGACUCCAUCGCGGACGUGAGCAUCAUGUACAGUGAGGAGCUGGGCACGCAGAUCCUGAUCCACCAGGAAUCACUCACUGACUACUGCUCCAUGUCCUCCUACUCCUCAUCCCCACCCCGCCAGGCUGCCAGGUCCCCCUCAAGCCUCCCCAGCUCCCCAGCAAGUUCUUCCAGUGUGCCUUUCUCCACCGACUGCGAGGACUCAGACAUGCUACAUACGCCCGGUGCUGCCUCCGACAGGUCUGAGCAUGACCUGACCCCCAUGGACGGGGAGACCUUCAGCCAGCACCUGCAGGCCGUGAAGAUCCUCGCCGUCAGAGACCUCAUUUGGGUCCCCAGGCGCGGUGGAGAUGUUAUCGUCAUUGGCCUGGAGAAGGAUUCUGGCGCCCAGCGGGGCCGAGUCAUUGCCGUCUUAAAAGCCCGAGAGCUGACUCCGCAUGGGGUGCUGGUGGAUGCUGCCGUGGUGGCAAAGGACACUGUUGUGUGCACCUUUGAAAAUGAAAACACAGAGUGGUGCCUGGCCGUCUGGAGGGGCUGGGGCGCCAGGGAGUUCGACAUUUUCUACCAGUCCUACGAGGAGCUGGGCCGGCUGGAGGCUUGCACUCGCAAGAGAAGGUAAUUCCUGUGGAAUGACUGUCACACAUCAGAGCUGGCUGGCCCGGGGCUGCAGCCUGACCCCUCUGCCAUCGGCCUCUAGUUCUCCAAGGACCUAGAAGACAGAUGGAGUUCUCCCCUGAACUCCUUGCUGCUAAGAAGUGCUGAGAAGUUACUCGCCUGGCGGUGGCUCCAGGGUUCUCUGGUUCUCUGGAGCAGAGUUCUCUGAAUACCCCAUCCCCCAACUGCUGAUUUUACAGCCCCAGGGAAGACAGUGGUAUCAGGCUGGGAGCGGCCUCCUCUGGCCUCCCCCAUCAGUUUGCAGGAGCAGGGGUGCAGGAUCCUGUUCUGAGCUGGGUCAAACAAAGCAGGGCCGGGCCUUCCUGCCAUCCCCAGGUCUCAGAUGGAAUUACACUAGAGGCCCUCCGCUGGGAAGCACUUGAGGUAGGGCAGGAGGGGGGCUGUGACCCCUGCCCUUUCCCCGCCAGAGACCUCAGGCUCUCAGCACAUUCCACAGGCUCCUGAGUCCCCGAGGCCUGGGCCAGCUUGGGCAAGCCAAGAUCAGAUGUCUCUGUGUUCGGGAAGGUCUCCGUGUGGGAAAGCCCUUGGGGGAUCCCGGGUGAGGAGUGUUGCCCCAUCCAGAGAAUGAAUGAGUUCCUUUAAGUGCCACCGCCAGCAAGCCCAGAGGCACACAGUCCGAGUGCACCCGCUUAGCCUUUACAUUCCUCUCCACCGACAAAAGGAAGGGGAAACUCAAUCAGCAGGACUUCAGAAAGGGCCUUGUGUUUAUAGCUUUGUCAAGUAAAUUUGGACGCAGCUGGAGCACAGGCCCUGUUUGUUUGCACAUAAUAAUCUUGUUUAUCACUUUAAAAAAUUCAGUAAUAUCUCAGCAGUCAGGCUUCUGGUUGUGAAAUCACAUUGUAUGGGAUUUAUACCAAAUUAUGUAUUUGCUAAACAUUCACUGCACACGUGUACAGCGGAGUACGAAAAGGAACGUUGUCCACAGGGGAUUUAUGGAUACAACAGCAAACAUUUUAUAAACUAUGCACAUGCAUUACACACAUGCACACACAUAUGCACACACAUGUGCAAACAUAGCCACUUUUUUGUCAAGAGUUACCCUUUGGGGCUCCUUAAACCAGAAUGGGAGUUUGAAAGAGAGAUCAUACUCCAGCUGAAGUUUGUUGACCCUUUUCUAAAAUUAAAAAGAUCAAAUUUAGUAUUUGCUGGAUAUGCAGGGAGAUGAGACUCUUUUAAUCUCAAAAUAAACAGAUUCUUUCAAGAACGAAGCUGUGGCCUCUGUCUUUUGAGCGCUUAUGACCACAGCACGGGCUCAGUCCCUCCCAGACCCACUCGCUGUCUGGGGAUAAUGGGCAGCCCCUCCUUGCCCACUGUGCCAACAUGCAGGUGGCCCCUGAGCAGCUUCCAUGGGUGGAGACGCUGCUCUGUCAGUCACAGGCUUGGAAAAAGCGAGUCCCCCCACUCUUUUUUUUUUUUUUUUUUUUUUUUUUACCAACCUGGGCACCAAGUCCCAGGGGGCUGAGGGUCUGUGCUUCCUGUCUACCUCCCUGCCAUUCUCUCACCCUCAUCCCACAGCAGGGUCUCAGGAGUCCCACUCUCCCUCUCCUCUCAUUCCAGUGCCCCACAACUGCCCAGUUAACCCCCAGAUGCAAGCCAGAUUCCAUCUGCCCCAGGCCCCAAGCUUUUGCUUUGGCAUCACGCGAGGCCAGGCUGCUUUGCAGGCACCAAAAUUCACCCUCUCCUACUCCUGGAAAAGCCCAGCCCCAGGCCUCACAGAGCCAGGGGAGGGGAUCUCAUCACAUCACAGUUAGAAAUCAUACAGGCCUAAAGUCCCAGCUACCCAGGAGCCAAGGCAGGAGGAACCCUUGAGCCUGGGAGUUGGAGGUUACAGUGAGCUAUGAUCACACCAGCUUUCUAGCCUGGGUGACAGAGCAAGACCCAACUCUUAAAAAAAAAAAAAAAAUACAGGAAAUGACUAAUGAACUUGACUCCAUGAAAUUGAAACUUACGUGGAAAAUUAGUCCAAAGCCUAAAAGACUAGCAACUGAGAAAAAAAAACAUUGCAACACAAAUGAGAGACAAAGACCUCACUUAUCUUCAUUACAGAGAGUUCGUAAUGUCAAUAAGAAACAGAAAACCGGAAAGGCAAACAGGUUAAGGGCAUGGGCAGCAAUUGAAUUACAAAGAAACAGACAGACCCUUAAACAUCAAUGCUUGACCUCACCCAACAGCAGGGAAACAGUCUCCACAACAGUAAAAUGUUGCUGGGAUGGGCCCAGCAUUCAGCAUGGUCCCUGCAACUUUGGCCUCUGCCCAGUGACCUCUGGCGGGUGUAGAAGAGCUCAUGCUUCAGUGAGGGGGUGGGGGGCACCCUGAGGACCCUGUCAACAUCAGCUGGACCACAGGCAUCUCAGAUAGAUGUCACUUACCACCCUCAUGUUGGCAGAGGGUGGUAACCAGCCAGCAUCUCCUUCUUAAACACCUACUAAGUGUCAGGCACUGUGACCGGAGACACAGUCAAGAAUCUCUGUGUUUUUUUUGUUUUGUUUUGUUUUUGUUUUUUGAGACGGAGUCUCGCUCUGUUGCCCAGGCUGGAGUGCAAUGGCGCGAUCUCAGCUCACUGCCACCUCCGCCUCCCAGGUUCAAGCAAUUCUCCUGCCUCAGCCUCCCGAGUAGCUGCGAUUACAGGCGUGCACCACAAUGCCUGGAUAAUUUUUGUAUUUUCAGUAGAAACGGGGUUUCACCAUGUUGGCCAGGAUGGUCUUGAACUCCUGAGCUCAGGUGAUCCGCCCGCCUCAUCCUCCCAAAGUGCUGGGAUUACAGGUGUGAGCUACCUGCGCUGGCCGAAUCUCUGCUUUUAGGAGCUCACUCCUCAUAGGUAGAGUUGACAAUAAGCACACAAACAAGUGAGAUAGCAGGGCAGCCGGACCACCCAGUUGGGCAAUUCGUGGCUUGGCCUAGGAACGUUACAUUUGACUGAGGCUGGCGAGGCCUGCAGCCUGCACCAGGAGGUACAAUGUGAGACUGAGGAAUGGGAAGAAGGCAUUCCAUGGAGCUCUGAGGGCACUGGGUGCAAGGGCCUUGCACAUGCAAAGACCCUGUUGUGGGUUCAAGCCACUGUGUGGGAGGGACAGGAGAGCCUGGCGUGGCUGCGGCCUUGAAGGAGGGGACUGUGCACACAGAAUUGCAAGUGGGGGUCUCCGCGGAAGCUCCUGGCAGUUUUAAGCAGGAUUAUUAGAUGAUUCAGUCAACUUUACAACUCACUUUGCUGAAUGGAGGGUGGAUUAACGAGGGGGUAGUUGGAGGCUACCCCUUGGAGGGCAUUCUGGACUUAUCUACCAAAAUUUCAAAUGCACAUACCCUCUGACCCAGCAGUUCCACUUAAGUAUUUGGUCCUGAAAUCUUGGUAAAAGUGCCCAAAGAUACAGAACAAGGAUGUUCACUAUAGCAUCUCUUAGAAUAUGGCCCCAAACAGGAAGCAACCCCAACCUCUAUCAUGAGGGAGGUCAUAAAAUUCCUGCACAUGCAACAGUGCCAUCCUCUGCAGCCUGUCAAAGAGGCAGGCAGCACUAACUGCUGGACUGGAAUGUUCUCCAAGAUAUAAUAAAUGCAUUUGUUUGAAAGCAGCUUGCAGCACAGUGCGUCAGGCCUCUGAGCCCAAGCCAAGCCAUCGCAUCCCCUGUGACUUGCACGUAUAUGCCUAGAUGGCCUGAAGUAACUGAAGAAUCACAAAAGAAGUGAAUAUGCCCUGCCCCGCCUUAACUGAUGACAUUCCACCACAAAAGAAGUGAAAAAGGCCGGUCCUUGACUUAACUGAUGACAUUAUCUUAUGAAAUUCCUUCUCCUGGCUCAUCCUGGCUCAAAAAGCUCCCCCACUGAGCACGUUGCCACCCCCACUCCUGCCCGCCAGAGAACAAACCCCCUUUUUCCUUUACCUACCCAAAUCUUAUAAAACGGCCUCACGCCUAUCUCCCUUCACUGACUCCCUUUUCGGACUCAGCCCACCUGCGCCCAGGUGAAAUAAACAGCCUUGUUGCUCACACAAAGCCUGUUUGGUGGUCUCUUCACAUGGACGUGCAUUAAAUUUGGUGCCGUAACUGGCGCGGGGGGAGGGGGGGGGGAACCUCCCUUGGGAGAUCAAUCCCCUGUCCUCCUGCUCUUUGGUCCAUGAGAAAGAUCCACCUACAACCUCAAGUCCUCAGACCAACCAGCCCAAGAAACAUCUCACCAAUUUCAAAUCCAGUAAGCAGCCUCUUUUUACUCUCUUCUCCAACCUCCCUCACUAUCCCUCAACCUCUUUCUCCUUUCAAUCUUGGCGCCACACUUCAAUUUCUCCCUUCUCUUAACUUCAAUUCCUUUCAUUUUCUGGUAGAGAUAAAGGAGACACGUUUUAUCCGUGGACCCAAAACUCCAGCGCCGGUCACGGACUGGGAAGGCAGCCUUCCCUUGGUGUUUAAUCAUUGCAGGGACACCUCUCUGAUUAUUCACCCAGGUUUCAGAGGUGUCAGACCACGCAGGGACGCCUGCCUUGGUCCUUCACCCUUAGCGGCAAGUCCCGCUUUUCUGGGGAAUGGGCAAGGACCCCAACCCCUUCUCUCCGUGUCUCUACCCCUUCUCCGCCUUUCUGGGGGGCAAGAAACCCCCAACCCCUUCUCCUUCACCCUGAGCGGCAAGUCCCGCUUUUCUAGAGGAGGAGCAAGUACUCCAACCUCAUAUCUCUGCGCCCCAAUCCCUUAUUUCUGUGCCCCAACCUCUUAUCUCUGUGCCCCAAUCCCUUAUUUCCAUGCCCCCACCUCUUAUAUCUCUGCACCUUGAUCCCUUAUUUCCACAUCCCGACCUCGUAUCUCUGCACCCCGACCCCUUUCCCACUUUUCUGGAGAGUAAGAACCCCUGAACCGCUUCUCUCCGUGUCUCUACUCUCCCUUUUCUUUAAACUUGCCUCCUUCACUGUAGGCAACCUUCCACUCUCCAUUCCUCCUUCUUCUCCCUUAGCCUAUGUUCUCAAAAACUUAAAACCUCUUCAACUCACACCUGACCUAAAACCUAAAUGCCUUAUUUUCUUCUGCAAUGCCGCUUGACCCCAAUACAAACUCAACAGUAGUUCCAAAUAGCCGGAAAACAGCACUUUCAAUUUUUCCAUCCUGCAAGAUCUAAAUAAUUCUUGUCGUAAAAUGGGCAAAUGGUCUGAGGUGCCUGACGUCCAGGCGUUCUUUUACACAUCAGUCCCUCCCUAGUCUCUGUUCCCAGUGCAACUCAUCCCAAAUCUUCCUUCUUUCCCUCCCGCCUGUCUCCUCAGUCCCAACCCCAAGCAUCGCUGAGUCUUUCUAAUCUUUUCUAUAGACCCAUCUGACCUCUCCCCUCCUCCCCAGGCUGCUCCUUGCCAGGCCGAGCUAGGUCCCAAUUCUUCCUCAGCCUCCGCUCCUCCACCAUAUAAUCUUUUUAUCACCUCCCCUCCUCACACCCGGUCCGGCUUACAGUUUCCUUCCGUGACUAGCCCUCCCCUACCUGCCCAGCAAUUUUCUCUUAAAAAGGUGGCUGGAGCUAAAGGCAUAGUCAAGGUUAAUGCUCCUUUUUCUUUAUCCCAAAUCAGAUAGCGUUUAGGCUCUUUUUCAUCAAAUAUAAAAACCCAGCCCAGUUCAUGCCUCGUUUGGCAGCAACCCUGAGACACUUUACGGCCCUAGACCCUAAAAGCCCAAAAGGCCGUCUUAUUCUCAAUAUAUAUUUUAUCACCCAAUCUGCUCCCUACAUUAAAUAAAACUCCAAAAAUUAAAUUCCGGCCCUCAAACCCCACAACAGGAUUUAAUUAACCUUGCCUUCAAGGUGUACAAUAAUAGAAAAAAGUUGCAAUUCCUUGCCUCCACUGUGAGACAAACCCCAGCCACAUCUCCAGCACACAAGAACUUCCAAACACCUGAACUGCAGCGGCCAGGCAUUCCUCCAGAACCUCCUCCCCCAGGAGCUUGCUACAAGUGCCAGAAAUCUGGCCACCAGGCCAAGGAAUGCCUGCAGCCCAGGAUUCCUCCUAAGCCGUGUCCCAUCUGUGCGGGACCCCACUGGAAAUCGGACUGUCCAACUCACCUGGCAGCCACUCCCAGAGCCCCUGGAACUCCGGCCCAAGGCUCUCUGACUGACUCCUUCCCAGAUCUUCUUGGCUUAGCGGCUGAAGACUGACACUGCCCGAUCACCUCGGAAGCCCCCUAGACCAUCACGGACGCCGAGCUGCCAGUAACUCUCACAGUGGAAGGUAAACCCGUCCCCUUCUUAAUCAAUACGGAGGCUACCCACUCCACAUUACCUUCUUUUCAAGGGCCUGUUUCCCUUACCUCCAUAACUGUUGUGCGUAUUGACAGCCAGGCUUCUAAACCUCUUAAAACUCCCCAACUCUGGUGCCAACUUAGACAAUACUCUUUUAAGCACUCCUUUUAGUUAUCCCCAGCUGCCCAGUUCCCUUAUUAGGCUGAGACACUUUAACUAAAUUAUCUGCUUCCCUGACUAUUCCUGGGCUACAGCCACACCUCAUUACUGCCCUUCUUCCCAAUCCAAAGCCUCCUUUGUGUCCUCCUCUUGUAUCCCCCGACCUUAACCCAUAAGUAUAAGAUACCUCUACUCCCUCCUUGGUGACCGAUCAUGCACCCCUUACCAUCUCAUCGAAACCUAAUCACCCUUACCCCGCUCAACACCAAUAUCCCAUCCCACAGCAUGCUUUGAAAAGACUAAAGCCUGUUAUCACUCUCCUGCUACAGCAUGGCCUUUUAAAGCCUAUAAACUCUCCUUACAAUUCCCCCAUUUCACUUGUCCUAAAACCAGACAAGCCUUACAAGUUAGUUCAGGAUCUGUGCCUUAUCAACCACAUUGUUUUGCCUAUCCACCCCAUGGUGUCAAACCCAUAUACUCUCCUAUCCUCAAUACCUCACUCCAUAAUCCAUUAUUGUGUUCUGGAUCUCAAACAUGCUUUCUUUACUAUUCCUUUGCACCCUUCAUCCCAGCCUCUCUUCACUUUCACUUGGACUGACCCUGACACCCAUCAGGCUCAGCAAAUUACCUGGGCUGUACUGCCCCAAAGCUUCACAGACAGCCCCCAUUACAUCAGUCAAGCCCAAAUUUUUUCCCUAUCUGUUACCUAUCUCAGCAUAAUUCUCAUAAAGACACACGUGCUCUCCCUGCCGAUCAUGUCCGAUUAAUCUCCCAAACCCCAACCCCUUCUACAAAACAAGAACUCCUUUCCUUCCUAGGCAUGGUUAGUGCAGUCAGAAUUCUUACACAAGAGCCAGGACCGCACCCUGUAGACCUUCUGUCCAAACAACUUGACCUUACUGUUUUAGCCUAGCCCUCAUGUCUCUGUGCAGCGGCUGCUGCCACCCUAAUACUUUUAGAGGCCCUCAAAAUCACAAACUAUGCUCAACUCACUCUCUACAGUUAUCAUAACUUCCAAAAUCUAUUUUCUUCCUCAUACCUGACAUAUAUACUUUCUGCUCCCCGGCUCCUUCAGCUGUACUCACUCUUUAUUGAGUCUCCCACAAUUACCAUUUUUCCUGGCACCGACUUCAAUCCAGCCUCCCACAUUAUUCCUGAUACCACACCUGACCCCCAUGACUGCAUCUCUCUGAUCCACCUGACGUUCACCCCAUUUCCCCACAUUUCCUUCUUCCCUGCUUCUCACCCUGAUCACACUUGGUUUAUGGAUGGCAGUUCCACCAGGCCUAAUGGCCACACACCAGCAAAGGCAGGCUGUGCUAUAGUACAAGCCGCUAGCCCGCCUCUUAGAACCUCUCAUUUCCUUUCCAUCGUGGAAAUCUAUCCUCAAGGAAAUAACUUCUCAGUGUUCCAUCUGCUAUUCUACUGCUCCUCAGGGAUUAUUCAGGCCCCCUCCCUUCCCUACACAUCAAGCUCAGGGAUUUGCCUCCACCCAGGACUGGCAAAUUGACUUUACUCAACAUGCCCCGAGUCAGAUAACUAAAAUACCUCUUAUUCUAGGUAGACACUUUCACUGGAUAGGUAGAGGCCUUUCCUACAGGGUCUGAGAAGGCCACCAUGGUCAUUUCUUCCCUUCUGUCAAACAUAAUUCCUCGGUUUGGCCUUCCCACCUCUAUACUGUCUGAUAACAGACCAGCCUUUAUUAGUCAAAUCAGCCAAGCGUUUUUUCAGGCUCUUAGUAUUCAGUGAAACCUUUAUAUCCCUUACAGUCCUCAGCCUUCAGGAAAGGUAGAACGGACUAAUGAUCUUUUAAAAACACACCUCACCAAGCUCAGCCACCAACUUAAAAAAGACUGGACAAUACUUUUACCACUUUCCCUUCUCAGAAUUCAGGCCUGUCCUUGGAAUGCUACAAGGUACAGCCCAUUUGAGCUCCUGUAUAGACGCUCCUUUUUAUUAGGCCCCAGUCUCAUUCCAGACACCAGACCAACUUGGACUGUGCCCCAAAAAACUUGUCAUCCCUACUAUCUUCUGUCUAGUCGUACUCCUAUUCACCAUUCUCAACUACUCAUACGUGCCCUGCUCUUGUUUACACUGCCAGUUUACACUGUUUCUCCAAGCCAUCACAGCUGAUAUCUCCUGGUGCUAUCCCCAAACCGCCACUCUGAACUCUUAAAUACAUAAUCUUUGCUGGCAGGACUAUGCUGAACCUCCUUUGGCACUCUCUAAUCAGAUGUCCUGAGUCAUCUCAAUUCUUAGACCUUUUAUACCUGUUUUUCUCCUUUACUUAUUCCGUUUAGUUUUUCAAUUCAUACAAAACCGUAUCCAGGUCAUCACCAAUAAUUCUAAAUGACGAAUGUUUCUUCUAACAACCGCACAAUAUCACCCCUUACCACAAGACCUCCCUUCAGCUUAAUCUCUCCCACUCUAGGUUCCCACGCCGCCCCGAAUCCCGCUCGAAGCAGCCCUGAGAAACAUCGCCCAUUCUCUCUCUCCACACCGCCCCCCAAAAAUUUUCGCUGCCCCAACACUUCGACACUAUUUUGUUUUAUUUUUCUUAUUAAUAUAAGAAGGCAGGAAUGUCAGGCCUCUGAGCCCAAGCUAAGCCAUCGCAUCCCCUGUGACCUGCACGCAUAUAUAAGCCCAGAUGGCCUGAAGUAACUGAAGAAUCACAAAAGAAGUGAAUAUGCCCUGCCCCACCUUAACUGAUGACAUUCCACCACAAAAGAAGUGUAAAUGGCUGGUUCUUGCCUUAAGUGAUGACAUUACCUUGUGAAAGUCCUUUUCCUGGCUCAUCCUGGCUCAAAAAGCACCCCCACUGAGCACCUUGCCGCCCCCACUCCUGCCCGCCAGAGAACAAACCCCCUUUGACUGUAAUUUUCCUUUACCUACCCAAAUCCUAUAAAACGGCCCCACCCCCAUCUCCCUGCACUGACUCUCUUUUCGGACUCAGCCCGCCUGCACCCAGGUGAAAUAAACAGCUUUAUUGCUCACACAAA